GCUCAGGCCCGUGGAUCUCAUCGAAGAUGGCGGCGCGAUCUGUGUCGGGCAUUACCAGAAGAGUCUUCAUGUGGACAGUCUCAGGGACACCAUGUAGAGAAUUUUGGUCUCGAUUCAGAAAAGAGAAAGAGCCAGUGGUUGUUGAGACAGUAGAAGAGAAAAAGGAACCUAUCCUAGUGUGUCCACCUUUACGAAGCCGAGCAUACACACCACCUGAAGAUCUCCAGAGUCGUUUGGAAUCUUACGUUAAAGAAGUUUUUGGUUCAUCUCUUCCUAGUAAUUGGCAAGACAUCUCCCUGGAAGAUAGUCGUCUAAAGUUCAAUCUUCUGGCUCAUUUAGCUGAUGACUUGGGUCAUGUAGUCCCUAACUCCAGACUCCACCAGAUGUGCAGGGUUAGAGAUGUUCUUGAUUUCUAUAAUGUCCCUAUUCAAGAUAGAUCUAAAUUUGAUGAACUCAGUGCCAGUAAUCUGCCCCCCAAUUUGAAAAUCACUUGGAGUUACUAAGCAAUUCGGAAGAGAAACACAUUGAAAUCACUGUCUUUCCCUGAGCAAGGGGGCUGCUCAUUAGAUCUUUUGAUACUUUACCAUGUGAAAUACUACCAGAACUGUUCUCUAAACCCACUUUUUCUGUAGAGGAAUGUAUCAUCUUUUUUUUUCUCAUAUUACAAAUGGACAAAUAACGGACUUUCUAUUUUCAUAUUUGCUGAAACCAUUUUUUAAAUGAAAUUAGGUCAUUAUUUAUGAAAAGUUUUGAGAGGGCACUGUCAACUUGGGUUUAAGACAGGAGGACAUUGCAAGUUCACACCUUUCAUAAGCAUAAAGUAGUUGCAAGAAAGUAUUUUCAUCCUGUUAGGAUUCAUAUCUAAGAUAGAGUUAUGCAUUGCACAUACACAAAUAAACUUUUAUUAGAUAGAUACCUAUAAAAGAAACAUAAAAGUAUGUUGUGUAUUACUGACAGUUCUAGAUUAAUUUCUUUUAGAAUUAAAGUAGAUUUGUUAAAGUGUAUUGUGUGUUGUAAAUUUUUUAAGUGAAAUUUGCUUGCGCUCUGCCUUGCCAUUUCUUUCCAGUAAGUAUAAUUUUGAAAAAAUUAGAAUAUAUGCCAAAUAUUGAGUGCUGUGACUCUUCCUCAUAAGAGAUGUGCCAGAUUCUAUGUCUAAUUGCAUAUUCUCUUCAGAGGAGAUGAUGCUUAUUUUAAACCUUUUUCUCUAUAACUUUUAAAAAGUGGUGCUGAGUAUUCACUAGAGUGGCAAGUCUUUGUGCUUUAAUGCACUCAAUUUGUGGAAAUUACUUAAAUAGCAGGUUAUCAGAUGGUUCUGAAUGACAAAGGUGUUAAAUUUGGGAUUUUUUUUUCAAGCUUUAGAUAUGGCUGGAGAGUAAUGAGACAGAAGGAAUGUCUUAUAUUGUUCUGACUGCUGACAAUUCCUAAAGAAAAGUGAUAGAAGGGUUUUUAACAAAAUAAGUUGCAUUUAUUCUCUUUCCCAGGGUUACUCCUUUGAAGAGGGCAAAAUUCAGUUGGGAAUAUAAAUUCUGGAAUCUUCAUGAAGAAAAUUAGUUAACAGUAUAGACAUGCCCUACAAAUAUCAUCCACAGGCACUUCAUUCAAGAACUUCAGGUGUCAGAGUGCCUGGAGCUCUGGAGCUUAGACAUUAGAGUUGAUUCCUUGGGGAUUGGUUCCAGGACACCUACUUGGAUACCAAAGUCCACAGAUGCCCAAGCCCCUUUUAUAAAAUGAUGUAGUAUUUGCAUAUUAUGUAUGCACAUCCUCCCAUAUACUUUAAAUCAUCUUUAGAUUACUUAUACUGAAUAGAAUGUAAAUAGUAUUUACAAUUGUGAAUACAAUGUAUUUAGUUAUGUAAAUAUGUAAAUUUUAAAGUUAUGUAAAUAUGUAGCUAUGUAAAUAGCUAUAAAAUAAUAUUUACAAUUGUGAAUAGUAUGUAAAUAGUUGUGAACAUAACUAUUGUGAAUAAUAUGUUAUAUGUUAUAGUUGUGAAUGUAAAUAGUAUUCACAAUUGUGAAUACAAUGUAAAUAGCUUUCACAAUUGUGAAUACAAUGUAAGUAGCUAUGUAAAUAGUGAAUACAAUGUAAAUAGCUAUGUAAAUAGUUGUUAUGCUGAUUAGGGAAUAAUGAGAAGGAAAAAAAGUAUACAUAUUCAGUACAGAUGCAGUCAUCUUUUUUUCCCCUCGAACAUUUUUGAUCCACAAUUGGUUGAAUCCACAGAUGGGGAACACACAGUCUUGGUAAAUUUAACCAACAAGGAGGGUAAACGCAUCCCAACAGGGAAGGUAAACUGCACAUCCAUCAGUACCUCUAGAGGGCAUCACUGGUUUAUAGCUCAAUACAGUGACUAUAUCAGAAUAAUGGCCUUUAGUUUUCCUGAAAGAUUAAAUUAGGCUUGCUGUUGUUGAAUGAGAUAAUCAAACAUAUGAUGUAAUUUUAAAGGGUUUACAUACAGAAGGCCUGCUGUAUGUCCUGCUUCUGCUGUGUAAAAGAUUCAGCAUGGAAUCAUUGGAAUUUUAUGUACAGGAUUUCAUUAUCUCAUUUUCUAUACAAUUUUUCCUUCUGAUCCAGAGACACGGAAAAACAAAGGGCAAGAUGGAAAUAAGGGAUGAGAAGGUCUAUGUGGAAAAACAGUUACAACUGGAGUGGUAACUGCAAAAACCAAGCAGCUUCAUGUGAUCGUUAGGACAGAAGAAAUUUCUCCUUUGUAGCCUAGAGCAAUAUUCUCAAAAUUUAAUGCGCAUGUUAAUCAUUUGGGGAUCUUUUAUUCAUUUUUUCAUGUGGGGAUCUUUUAAAAAUGCAAAUUCUGAUUUGGUAAGUCUGGAGUAGGUCCUGAGCUUCUGCAUGCUUCAAAAGCUGAUUAUGUUUUGAGAACAUGGAUCUAGAUGCUGGUAUUGAGGUGGGAGACAAGUACUGCCACCUGAAACAACAGUCUUGGUAAAUUUAGCCGACGAGGGUAAACACAUCCUAACAGGGAAGGUAAACUGUACGUCCAUCAGUACCACUAGAGGGCAUCACUGGUUUAUAGUUCAAUACAGUGAAUAUAUCAGAAUAAUGGCCUUUAGUUUUCCUGAAAGAUUAAAUUAGGCUUGCUAACUUGUUUAAUGAGAUAAUCAGACAUAUGAUGUAAUUUUAAAGGGUUUACAUUUUUAAAAAUUUAAUGAUUGCUACAUAAAAAGGGUAUCAGUUAACUAAUUUUACUUAGAUGGAACUUCUGUAAGCUUAGUAGGUAUGCUUAAAUAAAGCCUGCUAAUAAAAUAGAGAUUCAGACUCAAUAGAAUGGUUUUACAUAUGUAAUAUAUGUUUUAAACUGCAUAAAAUAAACUCCUCCCUCCUUUC